AUGGCCGAGAGGUCGGGUCAGGGGUGGUCUGCAGAGAGGCAGGCGGCGGUGCUGAGUCGGGAACCGCGCGCUCACCCGCCCAGUCGGACGGUUCCGGCGGGGGUGGGGUCGCCGCGGCGGCGCGCAGCACGGCGGGAACAUGGCGCGCGGAACCGGCGCACGCGCCUAGCUGGUGGGACCGUUAGCUCGAGGCGGACGCGGCCCGGACCCCGUGGAUAUGGAGCAGUGGCCGCCGCCGGCGCCCGAGCCGGCCCAAGGGCCGACCCCCGCAAGGAGCUGAAGGCGGCGGGAGACCGAGUCGCCGCCAGCGUUGGCGCCGUCAAAGAAGAUGGCCACGGAGACAGCAGCGUGGUCAGAGUGGUAGGAGCCGGCCAUCAGCGAGAGCUGCUCCAUGCCUGGCUGCUGGGUGCUACAGCCUGUGGCCCAUUGGCUUGCCUCACUGUGGUUGGUGGUGGCGGUGACAGAGACUGCAGCAUGACCAAAGUGGCUUUUCUGGCUUUGCCCGCCCAGCUGCUCCAUGCCAGGAGGAGGAGGAGACACCUAGAGCCUGCGACACCACGGCUCGCCUCGCUGCGGGAGGGUGGCAUCAACGGAGACUGCAGUGCACCAGAGUGGUAGGAGAGCGGCCGCACUAGGAGGGCAGGUGGCUGCAGCCAGGGUUGGGGGUCAGGCUUACAGCAAUGGAUGGGCUGCAGCAGUGGCCAGGUGGUAGGAGCCUUGUAGGGAGGGCUGGCGCAUUGGCAAUGGCUUUGCCCUGCCCAUGCCGUGGAUCUGACCCUGUACUGCCCUGCCUUGCCCUGUACCUGCCCUACUGUUACCUGGACUGUCUCGGCCCUGUCCUGCUCUGGUCCCAUCCUGACCCUGUCUUGGCCCUGUGCUACCCUGUCCUUGCCCUGGUCUUGCCCUGGCACUGGCCCUGCCCUGAACCUGCCCUGGCCUGACCUUGGCUCCGGCCCUGGCUCUGGCCCUGCCCCUUGUCCUGACCCUGGUGCUGUCAUGGCACUGGCCCUGCCAAUGGUCAUGGUCCUGCUCCUGUUCUGGCCCUGACCUGGCCUUGGACAUGUCCUGGCCCUGCUUUGGCCCAUCCCUGCCCUGGCCCCACCAUAGGCCUGCCUGUUCUACCCUCUCCUGGCACUGACCUUGCCCUGUCAUGGCCUAGUGGUGCCAUUGCCCUGCCUUACCCUGCGCUGGUUGUGCCUUGGCCCCGCUUGGUGCUGGCCGCUCCCUGGACCUGCCCUGACCCUGCCUUGGCUUUUGCCCUGCCCUCACUAUGGCCUGGCCCUGACCCUAGCCCUGGUCCUGCCAUAUCCCUGGCCCUGCCCUUAUCCAGGCCCUGCCCCUGCUGCUGCCCUGGCCCUGGCCUGGAACCUGGUCCUGUCAAGGACCUGCCCUGACUCUGCCAUGGCCCUGGCCCUGCUCUGCCUUGUUCCUGGCCCUGACCCAGACCCAGACCCUUUCCUGGCUCUGCACUGGCCUUUCCGUGGUCCUGAGCUGGCAGUGGUCUGCCCCUGGUCUUGCCAUCACCCUGCCCUGCUGUGCUCUGGAUGUGUCAUCACCCUGACCUGGCCCUACUCUGCCUUUGACCCUGCCCUGGCCUUACCUUGGCCCUCACCCUAGUCUUCGCUAGGCCCUGCUCUGGAGCUGGCCCUAGCACAGACCUGGCCCUGACCCUGGCCCUGGUCUUUGUCCUGCCAUAGCCCUGGCCCUGAAGUGAACUUCGAGGUGUCCUGGCCCCGGCGUAACAUAGCUCUGCAUUGGCAUGUCCCUGCCCUGCCGCUACCAUCGCCUUGCCCUGCUCUGCCCUGUCCCAGUACUGACCUGGCCAUGCUAUUUCCCUGCCCUACCCUGCCUUGGCUGUGCCCUGGCUCGGUUCUGGCCCUGGCCCCGGCCCUGCCCUGCCCUGGACAUGCUCUGACACUGCCUCAGCCUCGGCACUAGCCUGGCUCUUCUUUGGCAUCAGCUCUGCUCUCUGUGUGGACCGGCUCUUGUCCUGUCCUGCACUGGCCAUACCAUGCCCUGCCCUGCCCUGCCCGACUCAGCCCUGGCUCAGCCCUGGCCCAGCCUUGGCCUUGGCAUUGCCCCUGGUCCUGCCAUAUUUCUUGCCCUGUCCCUACCCUGGCCUUGGCCCUGACCCUUACCUUGCCCUGGCCCUGCCCUUGCCCUAACGCAGCCCCUGGCCCUGUCAUGGCCCUGCCCUGGACCUGUCCUGGCCCUGGCCCUUCCCUGCUUGAGACCUUGCCCUGGUUCUCCCCUGGCCCUGACCCUGAAAUGCCUGGCCCUACCCUGGCCUUGCACUGCUCUGGCCCUUGCCCUGACUCUGGUCCUGUCACUGGCCUAGCCCCAGCCCUGUUGCUGGUCUUACCGUGGCCCAGACCCUGCCUUGGCCCUUCCCUGACACUGUCCUGGACCCUGGCUGUGCCAAGAUCCUGCACUGACCGUGUCCUUGUUUUGCUCCUGCCCCAAACCUGGUCCUGCCCAGGCCAUGGCCAUGGCCCUGGCCCUGGCCCUGCCCUGGCUGUUCCCUGGCCCUGCCCUGCCUUGGCCCUAUGCUUUCCUGGCCCUGUCUUGCCUGUCCUGGCCCUGCCUUGGCCCUAGCCUGGCUUUGACCCUGCCCUGGCCCUACCUUGGCCUUCACCCUAGCCUUACCUGGCCACUCUGUUGGACCUGGCCAUAGCACAGACCUGGUUGUGGCCCUGGCCCUGCCAUGGCCCUGUCCCAGACCCUAGCCCUGCCAGGUACCUGUCCUGGCCCAGCUCUGGGCCUGGCUUUGUCCCUGGUUCUUAGAUGAACCUGGCCCUGCACCUGCCCUUGCCCUUGCCCUGGCACUGGCCUUGGACACGUCCGUGGUCCUAACCCUGGCCCUGCCCUGGAGCUGCCACUGUCUUGGCCCUGCCCUGGCUCUGGCCCUGCCCCGGCCCUGGCCCUGCCCCGGCCCCAGCCAUAGACCUGCCCUGGUUGGUCAUGCCCUACCUUAACCCUGUGCAACCCUGGGCCUGCUCCACCCUGCCCUGGCCCUGCCCUCCCUUUGGCCCUGCCAUGACCCUGCCUUGGCCCUCACACUGGCCCUAGCACAGACCUGGUCCUAUCUGUGGCCUUAGCCUGGCAUUGACCCCUGCUCCUGACCCUGGCCCUGCCAUGGCCCUUGCCCUGCCAAUGACCCUGACAGCCCUGGCCCUGGCCCUGUCUUGGCCUUGGCCCUGAACUGGCCCUGCCCUGACCCUGGCCCUGAAGUGGAUUUGCAGGUGUCUUGUCCAUGAUUUAACCUGGUCUUAUCAUGGCCCUGUCCCUCCCCUGGCUCUGUCCUGGUCUUGUGCUGACCCUGACCCAGACCUUGGCCCUGCCCCAGCCUUGUCCUUGACCUGGCCAUGGCCCUGCCUCUGCCCUGGACCAGCGCUGGCACUGGCAUGGACCCUGGCCCUGGCCGUUCACUACUUAAGGCCAUACCCUGGCCCAGCCCUGGUCCUGACCCUGUCCUGGCCCUAAUUUGGCCUGGCUCUAUCCUGGCAUGCUAUUCUGGCCCUGGCCCUGACCCGGCCCCUGUCCCUGUCCUGGCCCCAGCCCCAUUGCUGGUCCUGCCAUGGCCCUUGUUCUGACAUUGCCCUUUCCUGGUUCUGGCCCUGGUCUGAACCCUGGCCCUGCAAUAGACCUGCCUUGGUCCUGCCCAGACCCUGGCUCGGGCCCUACCUCUGCCCUGGCCAUACCCUUGCCCUGGCCUGGACCUCGGUCCUGGUCCUUGUCCUGCCCCAGCCAUGGUCCUGGCCCUGCCCUGCCUGUGCCCUGUUCUAUCCUGGGCUGGCCCUGCCAUGGCCUGGUCUUGCCAUUGCCCUGCCUUAGCCUGCCCUGCUUGUGCCCUAGAUCUGCCCCGGCCUUUGUCCCGUCUUGGUUCUAGCCUUGACGCAGCCCUGGACCUUCCCUGACCUUGCCUUAGCCCUGGCACUACCCUGGCCUUGGCUUGGCAUUUGCCCUACUCUAUGGCCUGGCUCUCGUCCUGCCCUUAUGCAGGCCUGACCCUGCCUGUGCCUUGGCUUUGGCCUGGACCUUGGCCAUACAGUGACCCUGCCAUGACCCUUUCCUGGCCCUGGCCUGGAACCUGGCCCUGCCAAGGACUUGCCCUGGCUCUGUCAUGGCCCUGGCCCUUUUCUGGAUUUGGAUGUGUCCUGUCCCUUAUUUCCCCAGCGCUUCCCUGGCUCUGCCAUACCCCUUCUCUGGGGUAGGGCCAGGGUCAGGACCAGGGUAGGGCCAUGGUAAGGCCUGAAGAUGGGAAGGGCCAAGGCAGCGGCAGGACCAGGGAAGGGUCAGGGCCAGGAAUGUGGUAGGACUAGGGGCAGAGCCGGUACUAGGGCUGAGCCGGGGCAGAGCAGGAGAGAUUACGUUAGGCUGUUAUGUAAAAUUUUUAUUUUAGAUUUUUAAGAUAACUACAGUAGUAGUAAUAAUGUCUAUACUAUGUUGUUUGUAAUAGUAAUAAUAUUUGCAGUAAAUAAUCACUAAAUUUUAACUAAUACUAUCUUUGCUUCCAGUAGUAUUCUAUGAGUAUAAUUUUAUCAAUAUGUAAAUAUGUGAGGCAUUGAUUCUCACAAUAAUUCUACAUGCUAGGUACUUAAAGCAUCCCCAUUUUCCAAAUGUAGGAAACAGCCAUAAAGAAGUUAAAUACUUGGCCAGAUUACUCCUGUAAUCCCAGCACUUUGGGAGGCCAAGGCAGGCAGAUGGCUUGAGCUCAGGAGUUUGGAACCAGCCUGGGCAACAUUGUGAAACCCCAUCUCUACUAAAAAUGCACAAAAAGAGCUGAUUUAAGUUUCUUGUAGGAUUCUGGUUAUAAAACACUGGUCAAACACACAGGGCAUGGAUAGGGCAGGGCCAGGGACAAGGUCAGGCCAGGAAGGGGCCAGGGCCAAGGCAGGGCCAGAGCUGGACUUGGAGGUGUCCUGGUCUGAUUUGCCCUGCCCCAACGUUGGCCCAGCCCUGCUCUGGCACUUCCUGUCAUGCCCUGUCCCUGGCCUGAGCAUUGGCCCUGUCCCUGUCCUGCUUCUGGCCCUGCCCCGGAGUUGACCAGGCACUACCAUGGCCCAGUCCUGCGUUGCCCUGCCCUCCUCUGCCCUGGCGCUGCCAUGGCCCUGCUUGGGCCCUAGCUCUGCCUCGACUCUGGACCUGCCCUGACUCUGCUCAGCCCUGGAUCUACCCUGACUCU